GAGCCGAGCUGAGCCUCGCCUAGCUCCGGCAGCCUCAGCUUCAGCACCAGCCGCACCGGAGCCCGGACCGCAGCCACUAAGGGCAGCGGCGGCGGCGGGAGCCAGGCGCGCAGCUAGCAGCGGCGCGGUCGGGAAGCAGCAGCCGCCGCCGCCGCCGCCGCCGCCGCGACGGGCAGCUGGGCUCGCCGGCAGCCGGCUCGGGCCCCUACCCUCUCGGCUACGUGUCUCCGGCGCCGGGCGGCCGGCGAGUCUGGAGCCCGCGCCGUCGCCGGCCGCGUCCUCCGGGCAUGGAAGGAGGCGGCAAGCCCAACUCUUCGUCUAACAGCCGGGACGAUGGCAACAGCGUCUUCCCCGCCAAGGCGUCCGCGACGGGCGCGGGGCCGGCCGCGGCCGAGAAGCGCCUGGGCACCCCGCCGGGGGGCGGCGGGGCCGGCGCGAAGGAGCACGGCAACUCCGUGUGCUUCAAGGUGGACGGCGGUGGCGGCGGUGGCGGCGGCGGCGGCGGCGGCGAGGAGCCGGCGGGGGGCUUCGAAGACGCCGAGGGGCCCCGGCGGCAGUACGGCUUCAUGCAGAGGCAGUUCACCUCCAUGCUGCAGCCCGGGGUCAACAAAUUCUCCCUCCGCAUGUUUGGGAGCCAGAAGGCGGUGGAAAAGGAGCAGGAAAGGGUUAAAACUGCAGGCUUCUGGAUUAUCCACCCUUACAGUGAUUUCAGGUUUUACUGGGAUUUAAUAAUGCUUAUAAUGAUGGUUGGAAAUCUAGUCAUCAUACCAGUUGGAAUCACAUUCUUUACAGAGCAAACAACAACACCAUGGAUUAUUUUCAAUGUGGCAUCAGAUACAGUUUUCCUAUUGGACCUGAUCAUGAAUUUUAGGACUGGGACUGUCAAUGAAGACAGUUCUGAAAUCAUCCUGGACCCCAAAGUGAUCAAGAUGAAUUAUUUAAAAAGCUGGUUUGUGGUUGACUUCAUCUCAUCCAUCCCAGUGGAUUAUAUCUUUCUUAUUGUAGAAAAAGGAAUGGAUUCUGAAGUUUACAAGACAGCCAGGGCACUUCGCAUUGUGAGGUUUACAAAAAUUCUCAGUCUCUUGCGUUUAUUACGACUUUCAAGGUUAAUUAGAUACAUACAUCAAUGGGAAGAGAUAUUCCACAUGACAUAUGAUCUCGCCAGUGCAGUGGUGAGAAUUUUUAAUCUCAUCGGCAUGAUGCUGCUCCUGUGCCACUGGGAUGGUUGUCUUCAGUUCUUAGUACCACUACUGCAGGACUUCCCACCAGAUUGCUGGGUGUCUUUAAAUGAAAUGGUUAAUGAUUCUUGGGGAAAGCAGUAUUCAUACGCACUCUUCAAAGCUAUGAGUCACAUGCUGUGCAUUGGGUAUGGAGCCCAAGCCCCAGUCAGCAUGUCUGACCUCUGGAUUACCAUGCUGAGCAUGAUCGUCGGGGCCACCUGCUAUGCCAUGUUUGUCGGCCAUGCCACCGCUUUAAUCCAGUCUCUGGAUUCUUCGAGGCGGCAGUAUCAAGAGAAGUAUAAGCAAGUGGAACAAUACAUGUCAUUCCAUAAGUUACCAGCUGAUAUGCGUCAGAAGAUACAUGAUUACUAUGAACACAGAUACCAAGGCAAAAUCUUUGAUGAGGAAAAUAUUCUCAAUGAACUCAAUGAUCCUCUGAGAGAGGAGAUAGUCAACUUCAACUGUCGGAAACUGGUGGCUACAAUGCCUUUAUUUGCUAAUGCGGAUCCUAAUUUUGUGACUGCCAUGCUGAGCAAGUUGAGAUUUGAGGUGUUUCAACCUGGAGAUUAUAUCAUACGAGAAGGAGCCGUGGGUAAAAAAAUGUAUUUCAUUCAACACGGUGUUGCUGGUGUCAUUACAAAAUCCAGUAAAGAAAUGAAGCUGACAGAUGGCUCUUACUUUGGAGAGAUUUGCCUGCUGACCAAAGGACGUCGUACUGCCAGUGUUCGAGCUGAUACAUAUUGUCGUCUUUACUCACUUUCCGUGGACAAUUUCAACGAGGUCCUGGAGGAAUAUCCAAUGAUGAGGAGAGCCUUUGAGACAGUUGCCAUUGACCGACUAGAUCGAAUAGGAAAGAAAAAUUCAAUUCUUCUGCAAAAGUUCCAGAAGGAUCUGAACACUGGUGUUUUCAACAAUCAGGAGAACGAAAUCCUCAAGCAGAUUGUGAAACAUGACAGGGAGAUGGUGCAGGCAAUCGCUCCCAUCAAUUAUCCUCAAAUGACAACCCUGAAUUCCACAUCGUCUACUACGACCCCGACCUCCCGCAUGAGGACACAAUCUCCACCGGUGUACACAGCGACCAGCCUGUCUCACAGCAACCUGCACUCCCCCAGUCCCAGCACACAGACCCCCCAGCCAUCAGCCAUCCUGUCACCCUGCUCCUACACCACCGCGGUCUGCAGCCCUCCUGUACAGAGCCCUCUGGCCGCUCGAACUUUCCACUAUGCCUCCCCCACCGCCUCCCAGCUGUCACUCAUGCAACAGCAGCCGCAGCAGCAGGUACAGCAGUCCCAGCCGCCGCAGACUCAGCCACAGCAGCCGUCCCCGCAGCCACAGACACCUGGCAGCUCCACGCCGAAAAAUGAAGUGCACAAGAGCACGCAGGCGCUUCACAACACCAACCUGACCCGGGAAGUCAGGCCACUCUCCGCCUCGCAGCCCUCGCUGCCCCAUGAGGUGUCCACUCUGAUUUCCAGACCUCAUCCCACUGUGGGCGAGUCCCUGGCCUCCAUCCCUCAACCCGUGACGGCGGUCCCCGGAACGGGCCUUCAGGCAGGGGGCAGGAGCACUGUCCCGCAGCGCGUCACCCUCUUCCGACAGAUGUCGUCGGGAGCCAUCCCCCCGAACCGAGGAGUCCCUCCAGCACCCCCUCCACCAGCAGCUGCUCUUCCAAGAGAAUCUUCCUCAGUCUUAAACACAGACCCAGACGCAGAAAAGCCACGAUUUGCUUCAAAUUUAUGAUCCCUGCUGAUUGUCAAAGCAGAAAGAAAUACUCUCAUAAACUGAGACUAUACUCAGAUCUUAUUUUAUUCUAUCUCCUGAUAGAUCCCUCUAGCCUACUAUGAAGAGAUAUUUUAGACAGCUGUGGCCUACACGUGAAAUGUAAAAAUAUAUAUACAUAUACUAUAAAAUAUAUAUCUAAAUUCCCAAGAGAGGGUCAAAAGACCUGUUUAGCAUUCAGUGUUAUAUGUCUUCCUUUCUUUAAAUCAUUAAAGGAUUUAAAAUGUCGUUGUAAGAUUAUUUAUUUCUAACCUACUUUUACUUAAGUCCUUUGAUAUGUAUAUUUCUCUAUUUUAUGAAGAGUUCUUGGAUUCAAUGGAAACAAAACUGAUUUUAAAAAGGCAACUCAAAUGAACUAGUAAAUAGCACCAAUCAAAACUUUCUUUCAUUAGCUGUGUCUCUGCAUCUAAAUUGUUAAUCAUUAAUGGUGGAGAAUUAAAUAACAAAUCCCAUUUUAUAGAUCUAAAUUGUAUUUCGGUGCUUUCAAUUUCAAAUUAGGUUAAAGAAUGCACUACUUGCUUGGCCACCGUAGGAGACUAGCAUUGCCACUGUUUGUUAAGAAUAUCACUAACCUCAAACAUGUUCAUUGAUCUUUCAGAAAGCUGAGGGAAAAUUAAUAUUUGUCUUCAUGUGUUAUCGGACUUUUACCAAGACUCGAUCAAUGUUAGUUGUAAAUAACUUUUUCAACCCAAAUAAAAAUAGCUAUUCUGUGUUGUAUGAAGGUAAAAGUCAUUGUUUAAGAAUUUAGUUUUAUUGCUUCACUUCAAAACUUAGAGUUUUAAAUUUUACAAAACCUGAUUGUGAGAAUUAUUCAAUUGUAAUGCAAUGGCUUGAAACCUACAAUAUUAUUUUAACCUGCAAUGUUUUAUGCAAAAUUGUAUGCUCGAAUCUACAAAUUGCUUGUAUUACACCAAAAAUCGUUACUUUUCUUUCUUCUUGCCAUAAUCAAGCAUCUGAAAAUAGUCCCUGCAUGCUUCUGGGGAAAAAAAAAUAGGUUCAAAUCAGUCAUUGUAGAGAAAGGCUUACAGUAUUUCUCGUUUCUAGAAAAGCAUAACAAUUCAUUAAUUGCCUAUCUUAUAAUUCCUAUAAGGCUGACUUGGAUCUCUGACUUAAGUCUAGAAGUGAGGUUUUCACUUUUAUUUAAUAUUAUUGCUAUUAUUAUUUAAAUAAUUAUUUGUAAACCACAGCUUGAUUUGGAGUUAAGUGUUGUCUGUGUCUUCACUGUAGCUGGUAAUUUACUAUGGUAUUAAUUUAAAGAAAUAAAUUCAAUACAGCAUCACGUCUGUUUGGGAACACACAUUUUGCUCUAUGUAUAUUGUAACUAAAUGGUUAGUAAACUUUAAGGCAUGUGGUGACUAACGUAGCCCUUAGAUAGGAGGUUUGUCAUUUUUAAUGUGUUGAAAAUAGUACAGACAUGGUGACAGAAAGCAGGGGUAAAGUUGAACGUCUAUGAGCAUUGUCUGUCUGUUUUCUUAACUCUUUACAUGAUCUGUGAGCACCUGCUUCUUCUCAAAGAACUCCCUUAGUAAUCAUUUGUGCCUAAUGCAUCCCACACAUGUGGAGUAUGACUGGAACACAAUUGAAAGAUUCCUAACAACUGGCUGCGGUAAAUAACCCAAGUUAAGAGCAUGACUUAAAGUGGAGGUCUUCAGUAUCUCUGGCACUGGCAAUACAUUUAAGAACAUACAGAGAUCACACAUUAUGUGGGACAGGGCCUGCAGAUAGACUUGAGGACAGAAAACAAAAACAAAAGCAGAAACUCUAAAGUGGAUCCUUGCUGCCUGUUAUGCCUUUUGUGGAUAUAAUACCUAUAAUACCAAAAUGAGUUGUUAUGUUUAAUUUCAAACAAAUCCCAACUGGUGUGGAAGUAAUUAACUGCUAGUCGAUGUAAUGUAAUCAUCAAUAUGCUGGUGACAUAUGAUGGCAUGUCAGGAAUACUGUUGUAAGAAAGGGAUUGUUCAGUCUACCUAGAACCUAUGGGAAAGCUGCAAGACCAUUUACAUAUCAGUACAAAACUCCUUUAUUUUAUUAAAAUAUGAGAAUUAACUUCAAUUUAUUAAGAUUACGUAUUGGUCCUUUAAAUUAUUAAAGGUUUACAUUUGAUAGGAUUAAUGGAUUUGGUAGUGAAAUAUUUUUAUAUAUAUAAAUUUUUGGUUUUUUAUUUUGAGCACUAUUGGGAAACAUAAGCAAAAUUGAAAUGCAUGGUCUUUCAGUGCAACCAUACAAUUUUUAUUCACUUUGUAAUAGAAUGGACAAAAAAACUAAGGUUUAUAUAUUAAACUAAUAAAAAGGUACAGGGUAAAUUAUAUACAUAUAUGUAUGAAUGUAUAUAUACUUAGAUUAAGAAAAAAAAAUGACUCACAUUCCUGUAAUAUAAAGGUCCAUUGCUAGUUGAAAAGUGACCUCUUUUCUCUGUACAUAGUGAAGCCCGUAUGUAUGGAGUUUUAAUCUGUACAGAAAGAAAUGUAUUAUUCAUUGGUCUUUCUGCUGCUGGAAAGAUAAUAGAAUAGCUGAUUCUUACAACAACUGUAUGAUCAGGGAUGAGUUAGAGUAUUUCUUUUGUCUUUGCUCAAAGCCAUACAUAUAUAAAUAUAUAUAAAGAUUAUUAAUAAAUUCAACAAAAAAUAAACUACAAUCAUGAAUAUUUUAUUUUAUCAAUAUAUGCUAAUCAAAUGUUUUAUUUUAUUAAUGAGUACAGCUUUGCCUCUAUUUUUACAUCAUAAAAUUUCCAAGAGCUUAUACUUGAUAAUCACAUAAAAUCAAUUAUAUUCUAUAAUUCUGGAAUGAGAGGACUUUAAAUAGAACAUGGAUUUUUCAACCACUUCUUUGUUUACCUUUUUCGUAUAGUAAAAUAUGAGCUUAUUUUCUUUUUUGCUCUGUGCCUUUUUAGAAUGUGGUUGUUCUCCAACUUCAAAACACAACCAUUUUGUGUAAUUAUUGGAUAUACAGAUGAGAAAUAAUUUUCCUGUAAUAAUGGUAAAUAAUUGUCCUGUAAUAUAUUUAUACAAACCUAUUUUGUUAUAAUAGUUCUAUGACAUACCUAUUUUGUUAUAAUAGUUUUAUAACAUACCUAUUUUGUUAUAAUAGGGCCUUGGGCUCUAUUAUAACAAAACAGGUUUAUAUAAAUACAUUCAUAUUUAUAGCCUUAAACAAAAUAGGUUUGUAUAGUAGGCCCAAGGCCCUAUUAUAACAAAAUAGGUUUGUAUAAAUAUAUUCAUAUUUAUAGCCUUGGGCCCUGCAAAGUUAUUUGGAGAGUGAUAGAACCUCCCCACACAAGUGGGUUUUAAAUGAUACCUAAAAGCCUGAGAUAGAGUUUAUCAUAAUGAGAAUAAGUAGUGAAGCAUUCCUGAAAACAAGGAGGAUAAAUAGUAGCAAUGGCAAUAUAUUCUAUUCACCAAAAAAGUAGCUUGUCUCCAGGUCUGGAUGACCUCUUCAUAAGUGAACAAUUCCCUGAUGAAUGCUGUUCCACUUUAAAGAGAUGGUUAUUUUGCAAUUUAUAAACUUAACUGAGCAUACUAUUUUCAGGACACUACAAAGUACAUAGUCAAGUUAUUACCGUCAUUCCUAUAGGACAGAGAAUGAUUUAAACAAUAUGACAUGUUUAAAAUUUUAGAUGAUUUAUUUCAAAUCCUGAAUUAUGUCUACUUCAAAUUAUGAGCAAUCUCUAUUAUCUUUCAGGACUAUUUAAAAAAUCUCCAUACCUCCUCUUUCAGCUUAGGUUUUUAUAUUUGUUAAUUUUACUAUGUUACUUUGCUUCUAUGGCCCUCACUUGCACUGUUUAUAAUGUUAACCUGUUUGAAUGAGAUAUCUCUCCAUUAUAUCUUUAUCUUUUUAGAACAUGUGCCAUAAAACCCAUGUGGUUAUUUUGUUCAUAUGCACUACAACUAGCAAACUUUUAUUUUAUGUUCACCUACUUUAAAAAGUACUCAUACUGUACCAUGGGAAAGAAACAUGGGCCUUAUAGAAUGGAAUGCUGAGCUAUUUUGAGUCCUGAAAACAAUGGCCAAAAAUUUAAGGAACUGUGGUUGCUGCAUGCACCAAAUUGUAGCACAUACAAAUAAAUAAAAUACAGUUCUAUAACUGUAUUCAAUAUGGUUAUUUUCAAGGAAAAAUAGGAUAGAAAUUUUCUUUGAAAGAUUUGCUAUUGUACUUAGGGAAGUACACCUGCUAUUACCCCUCAAAAGCAAUGACUUUCUUAAGCAAUUUCAAUUUUUUUCCUUUUUAACAACCCUGCACUUGCACAACCCUGCAUCUCUUGUCUCACCCUAAUGCUGACCCUGCUUCCAAUUCAGGCUUUGACAGGGACAAAUGGAGAUUUUAAGGUUUUUUAAUGAGAGAAGCCUUGCUGACACUCCCCGCAUCCCACCUUGAAAAUUAUUUAAAGAUGAUCUUAAAAGAACCUACAGAUAAUGCUCUGAAUUUGUUUACAAGGUCCUUGAUGUGGAGAGAAUGAGUAAUACAUUAAAUGCUGGGGAAAUAAUUAUCAUUUAGUGAAAAAUUAAGCAUGCUUUUCUAAAAUGUGGAUGUUUAACAGAGCACAGCUGAUUGGGAACACUGGCAGUUCAAUGCAGCUGGAGUGUCUCACAGGGUGAAGAGGAACCCAGAUCAAGUGGGAAAUAGGGAUUUCAAAAACCUUCUGAAAGGCUUUUAACAUCAGGGCAAAGGUUUUACAGUGUUGUACUUUAUAUUCUUAAUUUAAGCUUAUCAACGGGGAGGAUUCACAUUGAAAUGUCUGUUUUGCUAAUGUAACAAGGAAUAAAAUAAUUUAUGACACAGCAAAAACUGGGGGCUAUUUACAACCCCACCCUGCCUUGUGAGGAUGCUGGGUCCUAAGGAAGGUCCUAGGUUUGCUAAAUAGAGUAAUGGGAAUAGGAAACUGAAAGUUUACUUGCUUUGCGUAAGAUAAUAUAUUGCGGCAGGGAAGGGGUACAAGAAGAUAAGAGCUAGAACCUGUGAGAAGGGAAAGAAGUGAUAAAAUAAUUUUGGCUAAAAUAAAGCAAGUUCUCAGGCCAGGCGUGGUGGCUCAUGCCUGUAAUCCUAGCACUUUGGGAGGCCAAAGUGGGAGGAAUGCUUGAGGCCAGGAAUUGGAGACCAACCAGGGCAGCAUGUCAAGACCUGGUCUCUACAAGGAAAAAAAAUUUUUUUAAUUGACCAGUAUAUACUUACAUACCUGCAGUGUUUAGAAAACCCGACUAUAGGUGGUGUAUUCCUGUAGUCCUAGUUACUCAGAAAGUUAAGGCAGGAGGAUCGCUUGAACUUAGGAGGUCAAGGCUGCAGUGAGCCCUGUUCGUUCCACUGCACUCCAGCUUGGGGGACAGAGCAAAACCCUUUCUCAAGAAAAACCCAAACAAACAAAAAAGUGAAGCCAGUUCUUUAAUUUCUAUUGGAGAUAUCACACACGCUCCAAAGAGUGGCAAAGGUGAACAUUCUUUGGAGCUAUUAUAUUUCUAAUGUAACAUCAAUGGCCAUUUACUCCCAAAGGGAAACAUCUUUUUUUUUUUUUUUUUUUAAGAUGGAGUCUGGCUCUGUCACCCAGGUGGGAGUGCAAUGGCAGGAUCUUGGCCCACUGCAACAUCAGCCUCCCAGGUUUAAGCAAUUCUCCUGCAUCAGCCUCCAGAGUAGCUGGGAUUACAGGUGCCCGCCACCAUGGCUAGCUAAAUUUUUGUAAUUUUUAGUAGAGACAGGGUUUUACCAUGUUGGCCAGGCCGGUCUCGAACCCCUAACCUCAAGUGAUCCGCCCGCCUCACCCUCCAGAAGUGCUAGGAUUACAGGCCUGAGCCACCGCACCCGGCCCUGCUAUUUUUUUCUAUGUAGUUGUUUCAGUAAUACCAUAUGAGCAGAGAAUACUAUUGAUUCAUUCAAUUGAAGAAAUCUGAAUAAAUUAGUAAAUAUAAUAAUUCUUCAAAAGAGGACCACUUUAUGUUUCCAAUAGAUUAUAUAAUUGAAUUCAGGUAACGUAGAGUUAUUCAGACUUUUUUUUUUAAAUAACGGAAUUUUGCAAAAAAACAGGUUGCAUCGUUUUCUACAGAGAAUAUUCAGAUGUGUAGAGGCAAAGAGACUUUCUUGAAAGGUUUUUAUUUCCUGUUAAAUUUGUGAGGAAAACUCCUGAGAAAGGAAAGAUUUACUUUUGAAGGAAGAAAGAACAUAACCCAAAGAAAUUUGAAAGAUUCAAAAAGAGUUUUCCAAAUGUAUUCUCAUUUCUUUCUCAUAUUUGUUCAAGGUCUUAGUUUCCAAGCAUUCAAAAUUAAAUCUUGUUUGCCUAACUCUUCUAACAUCUAUUACCAACCUAACAUAUUACAAUUCUGUUUAAAAUGUGCAGUUCUAAAUGUUCUUGCGUGCCUCACUGUGGAAAGUGUGGUGCAUGGAACUGCAGCGUCAGUAUCACCCAGAAGUAUAAUUACAAGAAGUGCAGAGUCCUUGGCCUUACCCUGUACCUACAGAAGUCCGCUUUUGGGCAAGAUCCCCAGAUGAUUCAUAUGUGUAUUAAUAUUGAAAAAAUUGGAACUAGUAAGUCCUAGAGGAGGUAAAUUUUAAGGGCUUUUUAAGGGAACUUCCAAGUGUGAAGACAUUUCUGGAGAUGACAAGUCAACAUAGCAUGGGAUCUUGGCUAGACAAGGAAAGCGAGAGAACAUUAAAUAAACACAAGCAACGACAAACCACCUAUGUUAUAAUUUUAUCCUGGACCAUCCAAAGUUUACUCUUGGUCACGCUGUCUAACCCAGCCUGCCUCCUGGCACUUGCUAGUUAGAACCAGGGAAGAGAAAACUAAUAUGUGUUAGGUAUUAUAAUUUCCUUAUGUCACAUAAAUUUUGGUGCCAUAGCUAGCAAUGUUUCUUAAUAUCACAUCAGUACAAUGUGUCCAUUGCCUUCUGUAACAUUUUUAAUGCUAUCAAUAAUACAUUGACAUUAUAAAAAUAAAUGAAUGUGGUCAAUA